GCGUCACGUAACGGAGUGGCCAACGGCCUGCAGAGCAACAUGCCCAAGUUUUAUUGUGACUACUGCGAUACAUACCUCACCCAUGACUCUCCAUCUGUGAGAAAGACACACUGCAGUGGAAGGAAACACAAAGAGAAUGUGAAAGACUAUUAUCAGAAAUGGAUGGAAGAGCAGGCUCAGAGCCUGAUUGACAAAACAACGGCUGCAUUUCAACAAGGAAAGAUACCUCCUACUCCAUUCUCUGCUCCUCCUCCUGCAGGGGCGAUGAUACCACCUCCCCCCAGCCUUCCGGGUCCUCCUCGCCCUGGUAUGAUGCCAGCACCCCAUAUGGGGGGCCCUCCCAUGAUGCCAAUGAUGGGCCCUCCUCCUCCUGGGAUGAUGCCAGUGGGACCUGCUCCUGGAAUGAGGCCGCCCAUGGGAGGCCAUAUGCCAAUGAUGCCUGGGCCCCCAAUGAUGAGACCUCCUGCCCGUCCCAUGAUGGUGCCCACUCGGCCCGGAAUGACUCGACCAGACAGAUAAGGAUAGAGGGGAGGCCUUAUUGUAUCGGUUUUAUAUUACCUGUUCUGCUUCACCAGGAGAUCAUGCUGCUGUGAUACUGAGUUUUCUAAACAGCAUAAGGAAGACUUGCUCCCCUGUCCUAUGAAAGAGAAUAGUUUUGGAGGGGAGAAGUGGGACAAAAAAGAUGCAGUUUUCCUUUGUAUUGGGAAAUGUGAAAAUAAAAUUGUCAACUCUUUCAGUUAAAAGUGUGUUCCCUUUUUCCUCCUCUCUGUGUUCUCUGUGUAUUAUAAAAGAAAUGAAACAUUCCA